CCACAGCUCAUCUUGGAAGAGGGGUCCCAGAGAGGACUUAGCCUGGGUCUUGGCCUUGAAGAGCUUCCAGCCUGGUGUGGCCGACUUCUACUGAGACCUCCUCAUUCAUUUUUUGGCCACCUGUGGAGUAGAUUGUGGGAGCCCAGAGAAGGGUGUUGUGGAUUCUUCCUGGAGAUCAGACCGGAAAGCAUUCCUAGGAGAAGCAGAGGCAGAGUCUCACUAUGCUGUCCAGGCUGGUUUCAAAUUCCUGGAGUCAAGCAACCCUCUUACCUUGGCCUCCCAAAGCGCUGAGAUGUCAACAGAGGGAAAGAGUUGAAGUUCUCCAAUAUCCCCUUCUUCAUCUUCGGGCCACUGAUGAUGCUCCUGAUGCACCCGUAUGCCCAGAAGCGCUCCCGCUACAUUUACGUUGUCUGGGUCCUCUUCAUGAUCAUAGGCCUGUUCUCCAUGUAUUUCCACAUGACGCUCAGCUUCCUGGGCCAGCUGCUGGACGAGAUCGCCAUCCUGUGGCUCCUGGGCAGUGGCUAUAGCAUAUGGAUGCCCCGCUGCUAUUUCCCCUCCUUCCUUGGGGGGAACAGGUCCCAGUUCAUCCGCCUGGUCUUCAUCACCACUGUGGUCAGCACCCUUCUGUCCUUCCUGCGGCCCACGGUCAACGCCUACGCCCUCAACAGCAUUGCCCUGCACAUUCUCUACAUCGUGUGCCAGGAGUACAGGAAGACCAGCAAUAAGGAGCUUCGGCACCUGAUUGAGGUCUCCGUGGUUUUAUGGGCUGUUGCUCUGACCAGCUGGAUCAGUGACCGUCUGCUUUGCAGCUUCUGGCAGAGGAUUCAUUUCUUCUAUCUGCACAGCAUCUGGCAUGUGCUCAUCAGCAUCACCUUCCCUUAUGGCAUGGUCACCAUGGCCUUGGUGGAUGCCAACUAUGAGAUGCCAGGUGAAACCCUCAAAGUCCGCUACUGGCCUCGGGACAGUUGGCCCGUGGGGCUGCCCUACGUGGAAAUCCGGGGUGAUGACAAGGACUGCUGAGACCUGCCAGCCUCUUGACUAUCCAACCACCCAACAACUUGCCUGUGUCUUGAGAAGAUAGCCCCGGUCAGGACUUGCACCUGCGGGACACUCGUGGUUCCUUCCUCUGUUUCCCCUUCCGUGUCCUCCUUGUCCUGCGCUGCCCUGCCUUGAGGCAGAUGAUGGACUUUGUGACAUCUCUGAGCAGCAGCCUGGUGACUGUGGGGGGCUGUCUCGUGCAUCUCCCCUCCAUGACCCCCCCCAUCCUCUUUCAUUUCCUCCUCUGUGUCCACAGCCUCCCAGUGACCAUUGUCACAUGAGCUGGUGGGACUGUGUCACCAGGUACUGGGGUGACUGAAGGAUGUGGCAUCUAAAUAUUAGCUUCUAGGCUGGGAACGGUGGCUCACGCCUAUAAUCCCAGCACUUUGGGAGGCCGAGGUGGGUGGAUCACCUGAGGUCAGAAGUUCAAGACUAGCCUGGCCAACAUGGCAAAACCCCGCCUCUACUAAAAAUACAAAAAUUAGCCGGGCGUGGUGGUGCAUGCCUGUAAUCUCAGCUACUUGGGAGGCUGAGGCAGGAGAAUCGCUUGAACC